AGUGUCUAGCGGGAGCUCCGCGUGUAGCUACGCCGGCCGCCUGGCUUUGAGACAACGUGAUUCUCCGCAGCUGGUCGCCUACCCGUGAUGUUCUGCCCACGUCGAGACCUGAGCUGAAAUGGCAGACGAUCUCGGAGACGAGUGGUGGGAGAACCAGCCGACUGGAGCAGGCAGCAGCCCAGAAGCAUCAGAUGGUGAAGGAGAAGGAGACACAGAAGUGAUGCAGCAGGAGACAGUUCCAGUUCCUGUACCUUCAGAGAAAACCAAACAGCCUAAAGAAUGUUUUUUGAUACAACCAAAGGAAAGAAAAGAGAAUACCACCAAGACCAGGAAAAGAAGAAAGAAGAAAAUUACUGAUGUUCUUGCAAAAUCAGAACCAAAACCAGGGUUACCUGAAGACCUACAGAAGCUGAUGAAGGACUAUUAUAGCAGCAGACGCUUGGUGAUUGAAUUAGAAGAACUGAACCUGCCAGACUCCUGUUUCCUCAAGGCCAAUGAUUUGACUCACAGUCUUUCCUCAUACCUAAAAGAAAUUUGUCCUAAGUGGGUAAAACUUAGGAAGAACCACAGUGAGAAGAAAUCGGUCCUGAUGCUGAUCAUCUGCAGCUCGGCCGUCCGAGCCCUGGAGCUCAUUAGGUCGAUGACAGCAUUCAGAGGAGACGGCAAAGUUAUAAAAUUAUUUGCAAAGCACAUAAAGGUCCAGGCGCAGGUAAAGUUGCUGGAGAAGCGUGUGGUGCACCUGGGUGUAGGAACUCCGGGGAGAAUUAAAGAACUUGUUAAACAAGGUGGCCUUAAUUUGAGCCCCUUAAAAUUUCUGGUUUUUGACUGGAACUGGAGAGAUCAGAAGUUGAGGAGAAUGAUGGACAUUCCCGAGAUAAGAAAGGAGGUAUUCGAACUUCUGGAAAUGGGAGUGCUCAGUCUGUGCAAGUCAGAAUCCUUGAAACUGGGCCUUUUCUAAGUCUGUGUCCUAAUGAAGAUUCCAGUUUUCACAGUAGAAGUUGCAUCUUAUUUAAUGACUCUGAUACAUUGCAAGCACUCAGUAAAUAUCAGCAAAUAGUUUAUGUUAAUUGUGUCAACAGAUGGAUCACUGGAAUGUGGGGAUUCUGAAACAGAAAUGAAACUGUCCUUUUGACAACUCUCUUAUAUAAUAAAGUAUCACCGGCUUGUGUAUGAUCCUUGUUGAGCGGACCGUGUUUUUCUGUCACCAACUGGCUUCUGAUGUAACUGUGCAGGAGAAAGGAAAGAGCAGCUGGGUGACCUUAGGCAAGCGUAAGGUCUUGCCUCUCUGAGCCCCAUCUUAUCAACUCAAAGUGGGAAUGUCUCACAGCAUUGUUGAGGAUUCCAGGAGAUAGUACAUGGGGAGCAGAUUUGUAAACUCUGAGGCAUGGUCCCAGCAAAAAGGGUGGCAGGUAUAUUAAUCCAUUCUCACAUUGCUAUAAAGAACUACCCGAGACUGGGUAGAUUAUAAAGAAAAGAGGUUUAAUUGACUCACAGUUUCACAGGCUGUACAGGAGGCAUGGCUGAGAGGCCUCAGGAAACUUGGCAGAAGGUGAAGGGGAAGCAAGCACAUCUUCACAUGGCGACAAGAGAGCAAGAGAGUGAAGGGAGAAAUGCCACACACUUUUAAACGACUAGAUCUUGUGAGAACUCACUCCCUAUCAUGAGAACAGCAGAACAGCAAGGGGAAAAUCUGUCCCUAUGAUCCAGUCACCUUCCACCAGGUCCCUCCCCCAACAUUGGGAAUUAUAAUUCAACAUAAGAUUCGGGUGGAGACACAGAGCCAAACCAUGUCAAUUCCACCCCGGCCUCUUCCAAAUUUCAUGUUCUUCUCACAUUUCAAAACACAAUCAUGCCUUCUCAACAGUCCCCCAAAGUCUUAACUCAUUCCAGCAUUAACUGAAAAGUCCAACUCCAAAGUCUGAUCUGAGACAAGGCAACUUCCUUCCACCUAUGAGCCUGUAAAAUAAAAAACAAGUUAGUCAUUUCCAAGAUACAAUGGAGGUACAGGCAUUGGGUAAAUGCUCCCAUUCCAAGUGGGAGAAACUGGCCCAAAGGAGCUAAAGGCCUCAUGCCAGUUUGAAACCCAGCAGGGCACUCUUUGAAUCUUAAAGCUCCAAAAUAAUCUUUGACUCCAUGUCUCACAUCCAGGCCACUCUGAUGCAAGGAGUGGGCUCCCAAGGCCUUAGGCAGCUCUGCCCCUGUGGCUCUGCAGGGUACAGUCCCCAUGGUUGCUUUCACAGGCUGGUGUUGAGUGCCUACAGCAUAUCCAGGUACACAGUGUAAGCUGUCAGUGGAUCUACCAUUCUGGGGUCUGGAGGAUGAUGGCUCUCUUCUCACAGCUCCACUAGGCAGUGCCCCAGUGGGGACUCUGUGUAGGGUCUCCAACCCCACAUUUCCCCUCUGCACUGCCCUAGUAGAGGCUCUCCAUGAGGGCUUCACCCCUGUAGCAGACUUCUGCCUGGACAUCCAGGCGUUUCCAUACAUCCUCUGAAAUUGAGGCAGAGGCUCCCAAACCUCAGCUCUUGCCUUCUGCACACCCAUAAGCCCAACAGCACGUGGAAGCUGCCAAGGCUUGGGGCUUGCACCCUCUGAAGCAAUGGUUCAGCUGUACCUUGGCCCCUUUUAGUCACAGCUGGAGCUGGGGCAGCUGGGAAUUAGGCUGCCAUGUCCUAAGGCUGCACAGAGCAGCUGGGCCCAGGGCCUAGCCCACGAAACCAUUUUUUUCCUCCUAGGCCUCUGGGCCUGUUUGGUGGGGCUGGGGAGGGCUGCCACGAAGGUCUCUGAAGUGCCCUGGAGGCAUUUUAUCCAUUGUUUUGGCUAUUAACAUUUGGCUCCUCUUGUGCAAACUUCUGCAGUGAGCUUGAAUUUCUCCCCAGAAAAUGGCUUUUCUUUUCUACCACAUGGUCAGGCUGCAAAUUUUCAAGCUUUUAUACUCUGCUUUGCUUUUAAAUAUAAGUUAUCUCUGCUUAUGCAAAUGAGCAUAGGCUUUUAGAAGCAACCAGGCCACCUCUUGAACACUUUGCUGCUUAGAAAUUUCUGCCGGAUACCCUAAGUCAUCUCUCCCAAGUUCAAAGUUACACAGAUCCCUAAAGCAGGGGCACAAUGCCACCAGUCUCUGCUAAAGCAUAGCAAGAGUGACCUUUGCUCCAGUUCCUGAUAAGUUCCUCAUCUCCAUUUGAGACCACCUCAGCCUGGACUUCAUUGUCCAUAUCACUAUCAGCAUUUUGGUCAAAACUGUUCAACAAGUCUCUAGGAGGUUCCAAACAUCCCUCAUAUUCCUGUCUUCUUCUGAUCCUUCCAAACUGUUGCAACUUCUCCCCGUUACCCAGUUUCAAAGUUGCUUCCACAUUUUUUAGGUAUCUUUAUAGAAAUGUCCCACUUCUCUGGUACCAAUUUUUUGUAUUCUUCCAUUUUUACACUGCUAUGAAGAACUACCUGAGACUGGGUAGUUUAUAAUGAAAAGAGGUUUAAUUGACUUCCAGUUCCACAGACUGUACAGGAGGAUGGCUGGGGAGGCCUCAGGAAAUUUACAAUCAUGGCAGAAGAUGAAAGGGAUGCAACCACAUCUUGUGGCAACAAGAGAGCAAGAGAGUGAAGGGGGAAGUGCUAUACACUUUUAAACAAUCAGAUCUCUUGAGAACUCACUAUCAUGAGAACAGCAAGGGGGAAAUCUGCCCCCAUGAUCUAAUCACCUCCCACCAGAUCCCUCCCCCAACACUGGGAAUUACAAUUCGACAUGAAACUUGGGUGGGGACACAGCCAAACCACAUCAGCAGGGUAGUGGUAGAAAGAGCAUCAAGUGAAUUUGGCCCUUUGUAAACGUAUAAAAAGACAACAAUAUAAUUACAGCUGUCUUAUUAACUUUUUUUUAAAAACUUUCUAUUUUGAAACUUCAGGCUUAAUAGAAAAGUUUAAAAAAUAGAGAAUUCCCAUAUCCCCUUCCCUGAGCUUUCCCUGUGUUAAAUUCUUGUAUAACCAUAAUAGAGUUAUCAAAACUAAGAAGUCAUCACUGGUACUGUAUAAUUAACUAAACUACAGAGUUUAUUUGGAUUUCUCCAAUUUUUCCACUAAUGUCCUUGUUCUAUUCCAGGAUUCACUGCAGGAUCCCACAUUGCACUUACUUAGUUGUUGUAUCUUUUUGGUUUCUUCAGACCAGUGACAGUUCCUCAGUAUUUCCCUGUCUUUCAUGACCUUCACACUUUUGAACAGUAUCCAUCGUGUAUUUUGUAGAAUGUCCUUCAAUUUGGAUUUGUCUGUAAUGUUCUCAUGAUUUGAUUAAAGUUAUGCAUUUUUUGACCAGAA